GUUUGCGUUUGAACCUCUUGGCGGGUGCCGGCCAUGGCGGCUUCGCUCCCGGGACCUGGGAGCCGGCUUUUCCGCACAUAUGGGGCUGCGGACGGCAGGAGACAGCGGCGGCCGGGCCGGGAAGCCGCGCAGUGGUUCCCGCCGCAGGACCGGAGGCGUUUCUUCAACAGCAGCGGCAGCAGCGACGCCAGCAUCGGCGACCCCUCGCAGUCCGACGAUCCUGACGAUCCCGACGACCCCGACUUCCCCGGCAGCCCGGUGAGGCGGCGGCGGAGGCGUCCCGGCGGCCGAGUGCCCAAGGACCGGCCCAGCCUGACCGUGACCCCAAAGCGCUGGAAGCUGCGAGCUCGCCCAAGCCUAACCGUGACCCCAAGACGCCUGGGGCUGCGAGCUCGGCCCCCGCAGAAGUGCAGCACACCCUGCGGCCCGCUCCGACUUCCGCCCUUCCCCAGCCGCGACUCCGGCCGCCUCAGCCCGGACCUCAGCGUGUGCGGCCAGCCCAGGGACGGCGACGAGCUGGGCAUCAGUGCCUCCCUGUUCAGCUCUCUGGCCUCGCCCUGCCCCGGGUCCCCAACGCCAAGGGACAGUGUCAUCUCGAUCGGCACCUCCGCCUGUCUGGUUGCAGCCUCAGCCGUCCCGAGCGGCCUCCACCUCCCAGAAGUCUCCCUGGACCGAGCAUCUCUCCCCUGCUCCCAGGAGGAAGCGACAGGAGGAGCCAAGGACACCAGGAUGGUCCACCAAACCCGCGCCAGCCUCAGGUCAGUUCUCUUUGGCCUUAUGAACUCAGGAACCCCUGAGGAUUCUGAGUUUCGGGCAGAUGGGAAGAAUAUGAGAGAGUCCUGCUGUAAAAGGAAACUGGUGGUGGGAAAUGGACCAGAGGGUCCAGGUCUGUCAAGCACAGGCAAGAGGAGGGCCACAGGCCAGGACUCUUGUCAAGAGAGAGGGCUUCAAGAGGCCGUCCGGAGAGAGCAUCAGGAGGCCAGUGUUCCCAAGGGCCGCAUUGUGCCAAGGGGAAUAGACAGGCUGGAGAGAACUAGAUCAAGCCGGAAGAGCAAACAUCAGGAGGCAACGGAAACCUCUCUCCUCCAUUCCCACCGCUUUAAAAAGGGCCAAAAGCUGGGAAAAGAUUCGUUCCCCACCCAGGACCUGACUCCUUUACAGAAUGUCUGCUUUUGGACCAAAACCAGGGCUUCCUUCAGUUUCCACAAGAAGAAAAUUGUGACUGAUGUGUCAGAGGUCUGCAGCAUCUAUACCACUGCCACUUCUCUCUCUGGAUCCCUCCUAUCAGAAUGUUCAAACCGGCCUGUCAUGAACAGAACAAGUGGUGCUCCGUCCUCUUGGCACUCCUCCUCUAUGUAUUUGCUAAGCCCCUUAAACACUCUAAGUAUUUCAAACAAAAAGGCAUCUGAUGCUGAAAAGGUUUAUGGGGAAUGCAGUCAGAAGGGUCCUGUCCCCUUUAGCCAUUGCCUUCCCACAGAAAAACUGCAACGCUGUGAGAAGAUUGGGGAAGGGGUGUUUGGCGAAGUGUUUCAAACAAUUGCUGAUCACACACCCGUAGCCAUAAAAAUCAUUGCUAUUGAAGGACCAGAUUUAGUCAAUGGAUCCCAUCAGAAAACCUUUGAGGAAAUCCUGCCAGAGAUCAUCAUCUCCAAAGAGUUGAGCCUCUUAUCCGGUGAAGUGUGCAACCGCACAGAAGGCUUUAUCGGGCUGAACUCAGUGCACUGUGUCCAGGGAUCUUACCCUCCCUUGCUCCUCAAAGCCUGGGAUCACUAUAAUUCAACCAAAGGCUCUGCAAAUGACCGGCCUGAUUUUUUUAAAGACGACCAGCUCUUCAUUGUGCUGGAAUUUGAGUUUGGAGGGAUUGACUUAGAGCAAAUGCGAACCAAGUUGUCUUCCUUGGCUACUGCAAAGAGCAUUCUACACCAGCUCACAGCCUCCCUCGCAGUGGCAGAGGCAUCACUGCGCUUUGAGCACCGAGACUUACACUGGGGGAACGUGCUCUUAAAGAAAACCAGCCUCAAAAAACUCCACUACACCCUCAAUGGGAAGAGCAGCACUAUCCCCAGCUGUGGGUUGCAAGUGAGCAUCAUUGACUACACCCUGUCGCGCUUGGAACGGGAUGGGAUUGUGGUUUUCUGUGACGUUUCCAUGGAUGAGGACCUGUUUACCGGUGACGGUGACUACCAGUUUGACAUCUACAGGCUCAUGAAGAAGGAGAAUAACAACCGCUGGGGUGAAUAUCACCCUUAUAGUAAUGUGCUCUGGUUACAUUACCUGACAGACAAGAUGCUGAAACAAAUGACCUUCAAGACUAAAUGUAACACUCCUGCCAUGAAGCAAAUUAAGAGAAAAAUCCAGGAGUUCCACAGGACAAUGCUGAACUUCAGCUCUGCCACUGACUUGCUCUGCCAGCACAGUCUGUUUAAGUAAGCUAAAUGUAUCUUACUGCCCCGAAAUGAGAGGAGACUGGUCUUGAAGCCUCUGGUGCUGUUUCAACCUCCAUCCCCACAGGAGGGUGGAACUCCCAUUCUCACAGGUUUCCAGUCAGCUUUUCAAACAAGAAUUUUGUUUCCAAAUGGAAACUGAAAUAUUUGUUGAAAUGUUUAAAUUUGCUGAUAACAAAUGUUCUGAAAGAAGUAAACUAGCCGGGCACAGUGGCGUGCGCCUGUAGUCCCAGCUACUCGGGAGGCUGAGGCAGGAGGAUCGCUUGAGCCCAAGAGUUCAUAUCUAGCCUGGUCAACAUAGCAAGACCCCUGUCUCUAUUUUUUUAAAUAAAUAAACUACAUGUGAAAACAAA